ACCCGGCCCGGCGGCUCCGCGCUCGCUCCCUCGCUCGCUCCCUCGCUGUGUCUGGCAGGCUGCGGCCGCCGCUGGGCUGCUGCCAUGGGGAGCCGUUGAGAGUGGGGCCCUCUUCGCUCCGCCGCGCUCCUCCGGCUGCCAGCGGGGGUGGGCGGGAGGGAGGGGCGGGGGGGAGCGGGCGACGGAGCCGGGAUUGGGGGGUGGGGGGGCCGGGAGGGAGGGGGGCAAGAGCCGGAGGAAGCCCACCAAGUCCGGCGGCGGCGGCGGCGGCCGGGAGGAGGAGGAGGAGGAGGCGGAGGACGCGGCGGCGGCGGGGACGCGGUGACUUAGGGCCGCUCCGUGUUAUGAAGACAGUAUGGAGUUUCCAGACCAUAGUAGACAUUUGCUACAGUGUCUGAGCGAGCAGAGACACCAGGGUUUUCUUUGUGACUGCACUGUUCUGGUGGGAGAUGCCCAGUUCCGAGCGCACCGAGCUGUACUGGCUUCAUGCAGCAUGUAUUUCCACCUCUUUUACAAGGACCAGCUGGACAAAAGAGACAUUGUUCAUCUGAACAGCGACAUUGUUACAGCCCCCGCUUUCGCUCUCCUGCUUGAAUUCAUGUAUGAAGGGAAACUCCAGUUCAAAGACUUGCCCAUUGAAGACGUGCUAGCAGCUGCCAGUUAUCUCCACAUGUAUGACAUUGUCAAAGUCUGCAAAAAGAAGCUGAAAGAGAAAGCCACCACGGAGGCAGACAGCACCAAAAAGGAAGAAGAUGCUUCAAGUUGUUCGGACAAAGUCGAGAGUCUCUCCGAUGGCAGCAGCCACAUAGCAGGCGAUUUGCCCAGUGAUGAAGAUGAAGGAGAAGAUGAAAAAUUGAACAUCCUGCCCAGCAAAAGGGACUUGGCGGCCGAGCCUGGGAACAUGUGGAUGCGAUUGCCCUCAGACUCAGCAGGCAUCCCCCAGGCUGGCGGAGAGGCAGAGCCACACGCCACAGCAGCUGGAAAAACAGUAGCCAGCCCCUGCAGCUCAACAGAGUCUUUGUCCCAGAGGUCUGUCACCUCCGUGAGGGAUUCGGCAGAUGUUGACUGUGUGCUGGACCUGUCUGUCAAGUCCAGCCUUUCAGGAGUUGAAAAUCUGAACAGCUCUUAUUUCUCUUCACAGGACGUGCUGAGAAGCAACCUGGUGCAGGUGAAGGUGGAGAAAGAGGCUUCCUGUGAUGAGAGUGAUGUUGGCACUAAUGACUAUGACAUGGAACAUAGCACUGUGAAAGAAAGUGUGAGCACUAAUAACAGGGUACAGUAUGAGCCGGCCCAUCUGGCUCCCCUGAGGGAGGACUCGGUCUUGAGGGAGCUGGACCGGGAGGACAAAGCCAGUGAUGAUGAGAUGAUGACCCCAGAGAGCGAGCGUGUCCAGGUGGAGGGAGGCAUGGAGAGCAGUCUGCUCCCCUACGUCUCCAACAUCCUGAGCCCCGCGGGCCAGAUCUUCAUGUGCCCCCUGUGCAACAAGGUCUUCCCCAGCCCCCACAUCCUGCAGAUCCACCUGAGCACGCACUUCCGCGAGCAGGACGGCAUCCGCAGCAAGCCCGCCGCCGAUGUCAACGUGCCCACGUGCUCGCUGUGUGGGAAGACUUUCUCUUGCAUGUACACCCUCAAGCGCCACGAGAGGACUCACUCGGGGGAGAAGCCCUACACAUGCACCCAGUGCGGCAAGAGCUUCCAGUACUCGCACAACCUGAGCCGCCAUGCCGUGGUGCACACCCGCGAGAAGCCGCACGCCUGCAAGUGGUGCGAGCGCAGGUUCACGCAGUCCGGGGACCUGUACAGACACAUUCGCAAGUUCCACUGUGAGUUGGUGAACUCCUUGUCGGUCAAAAGCGAAGCACUGAGCUUGCCUACUGUCAGAGACUGGACCUUAGAAGAUAGCUCUCAAGAACUUUGGAAAUAAUUUUAUAUAUAUAUAAAUAAUAUAUAUAUAUAUACAUAUAUAUAAAUAGAUCUCUAUAUAGUUGUGGUACGGUCUAAAAGCAGUCUUGUUUCCUGGAAAUAAAAAGUUGGGAUAUUAACUUGUUUUUGCACUUUAGAAUAGCAUGAGAAUCUCACUAAUUUAGCAUUCUGAUAAAAGAAACUUUAGAGCAAGUCAGAAUAGAGAGGUGUUUUUCCUUUGAGGGGAUAGGGGAAGUAAGCCAAUAAGAACCUUUUAAACAAAUCGUCCUGUCACAAAAUGCUUUCAUAUGGCUUAAUUUUGUCAACACUGCAUUGUCUUUUGAGCUCUUUUUUCCCCCCCAACAAAGUUUUUUUGUUUUUUGUUUUUUUUUUUAAGUAGAAAUUCCCUCCAGUUUUAUUAGCCUCUUUAUAUGUCUCAAAUUGCAUGAAUUUUUUCUGGCUGUUGGAAACCUGAAUGCUUUUAGACCCAAAUGGAAAAUUUCUGAAAUGCUGGAUUAUCUAUUUUUAAACAAGCAGUUGACUUAAAACUUUCUGUGGCAACUUCUGGUUUUCUGACAGUUCCCAGUGAGAGAAAUGCUGAAAGUACACUGGGAUCACUGGGACACUGUCUUAUGAAGGUUUGCUUGGGAUGAAAAAGGAUAUUGCAGCUUCAGCAGUGUUGAACUGUGUGUUUAAAAAUGUGAAUUACUGUUAUUGUAUACUGUAAUUGAUUACAUGGGCUGGGGGGGUGUCAAAGAACUUGACAGGUUGUGUUGAUGCUCUUAGUUGAGUCUUGAAAAGUAAAUAUUAACGCUACAGAAAUGCAUGAGUUUCAAUAUAUUUUUUGUCUUUGUUUGCAUUGUAUAACUUUAACGAGUGAGUUUAAAAUUAUUUAAUUUCCUUAGAAAAAUAACACCAUUUGGAAAAAAAAACUGGUGUUAUGAAGAACGUAAAUGCACUGUUUUUAUUUUUAUUUUAUAUAAUUUAAAUUGACUUUCCCACUGUCUUUAAGUUGAAACUGUUAAGCUGAAUAAAAACUUAAGCUGCAAAUUGAUAACUUCGCUACAUAACAAGGAAAAUAUAAAUGUUUACAAACAGCUUAAAGAUUUGCAUGUGCAGUGUGCAUUUAUAACAAACUUCUAAUUGCACAAAACCCAUGCCAGCUCAGAGUUUAGGUGUACACAUUUACCCAGUUGAGCGUUCUUAGAAUAACUACUGCACAAGUUGACAAUAGGUCGUUCUCUCUUUUUUUUUGUUUGCUCCCUUUUUCUUUUUCUCCCCUUCCUCCUUACCCUCCCUCCCUUACUCUCCCCCCCCACCACCACCCUCCACCCCCAACUCAUGAAAAGAUUCUAUGGACUGAAAAAGCCCCAGGCUGAAAGGACUGGACUGCCUUGAUUGACAUGGGGAAGGGGGUUAGUAGACUAUGUGGAUUGCGGCAGCAGAGGCUGCAGCCUAACGUGUGGUUUUAAUGACCAGCACGCAAGGCAAAAGCAUUUUGCACAGUGUUUGUUUUCCUGUCUUGCACUUACAAAUAAGGUCUAUGGGAGUAGCAUGGAAAACGUUUGCUGUUUUUCCCUUUUUUUUUUAAUUGCUUUUGUUUAAAAUUUGAUCGCCUUAACUACUGUAAACAUAGCCUAUUUUUGUGCUUAAGAUACUGAAUGGAAAACUCCAUUGUGUGUUGCUGGACUGUUUUGGAAAUAUUUGGUUAAAUGUGUGUUAAUUUGGCUGUAAUGGCAUUUAAAGCAAACAAACAAACAAAAAAAGCUGUGAAAAUGGCCUUGGAGCAUUAUCUUUAGUUACUUGAAGAGUUUCUAGUUUUUUUAAAAUACAGUUUAUGUUAAAAUAAUUUUUAUUAAUUUAGAGAAGACAAUCAAUGUCUGUGAGAAAACGGACUUUCUUUUGGAUUUUCUUUUUGUGGUCAUUGUGAGUGAUUGCUUUUUCCUUUUCUUAGUUUCACAUUCUUCCUUUGUUCUAAAACUUAGACUGACAUCUAGCUUUGACAAUCAUAGUAUGUUUUAUUUUCCUGAGGGGGAAUAACUUAUAAUGCUGUUUAGUUUUGUACUAUUGGUGUGUUGGUGAAUUUUUAAACUGUGUGCUAACUGCAAUAAAUUAUAUGAACUGAGAA